GACAGUGGCGCCGGAAGCCGGGGCCGGGGCUGCGGGGCGAGGUGAGAGCGGGCGGGCUUGGGAGCCGGCAGGUGCGGGCCGAGGGCGGGCACAGCGGCCGGCGGAGCUGAGGCGCGCGGCGGGGAAAGCUCGGCCGGCCUCCCGGGCCCCAGCCUUCUCCAGAACCCCUGCUACCCACGACUAAGCCCCGAACAAUCUGCCCUUGGGCUUGUUCUCUUCGCAGUUGUCGGCCCUGGGCCGGGAGCUGGAGUCCCAGACUCAUAGGUCCCGGCCCAGCCCCCGAAGAGCCGCCUCAGCCGGGGGGAGUUGCUCGGACUCAAACGUCCAGUCCUCGUGCGACCGCGCUGGGUCGGAAGUGAGCAGGCUGAGGCCACCAUGGAGCAGUGUGCGUGCGUGGAGAGAGAGCUGGACAAGGUCCUGCAGAAGUUCCUGACCUACGGGCAGCACUGUGAGCGGAGCCUGGAGGAGCUGCUGCACUACGUGGGCCAGCUGCGGGCUGAGCUGGCCAGCGCAGCCCUCCAGGGGACCCCUCUCUCAGCCACCCUCUCUCUGGUGAUGUCACAGUGCUGCCGGAAGAUCAAAGAUACGGUGCAGAAACUGGCUUCGGACCAUAAGGACAUUCACAGCAGUGUAUCCCGAGUGGGCAAAGCCAUUGACAGGAACUUCGACUCUGAGAUCUGUGGUGUUGUGUCAGAUGCGGUGUGGGACGCGCGGGAACAGCAGCAGCAGAUCCUGCAGAUGGCCAUCGUGGAACACCUGUAUCAGCAGGGCAUGCUCAGCGUGGCCGAGGAGCUGUGCCAGGAAUCAACGCUGAAUGUGGACUUGGAUUUCAAGCAGCCUUUCCUAGAGUUGAAUCGAAUCCUGGAAGCCCUGCACGAACAAGACCUGGGUCCUGCGUUGGAAUGGGCCGUCUCCCACAGGCAGCGCCUGCUGGAACUCAACAGCUCCCUGGAGUUCAAGCUGCACCGACUGCACUUCAUCCGCCUCUUGGCAGGAGGCCCCGCGAAGCAGCUGGAGGCCCUCAGCUAUGCUCGGCACUUCCAGCCCUUUGCUCGGCUGCACCAGCGGGAGAUCCAGGUGAUGAUGGGCAGCCUGGUGUACCUGCGGCUGGGCUUGGAGAAGUCACCCUACUGCCACCUGCUGGACAGCAGCCACUGGGCAGAGAUCUGUGAGACCUUUACCCGGGACGCCUGUUCCCUGCUGGGGCUUUCUGUGGAGUCCCCCCUUAGCGUCAGCUUUGCCUCUGGCUGUGUGGCGCUGCCUGUGUUGAUGAACAUCAAGGCUGUGAUUGAGCAGCGGCAGUGCACUGGGGUCUGGAAUCACAAGGACGAGUUACCGAUUGAGAUUGAACUAGGCAUGAAGUGCUGGUACCACUCCGUGUUCGCUUGCCCCAUCCUCCGCCAGCAGACGUCAGAUUCCAACCCUCCCAUCAAGCUCAUCUGUGGCCAUGUUAUCUCCCGAGAUGCACUCAAUAAGCUCAUUAAUGGAGGAAAGCUGAAGUGUCCCUACUGUCCCAUGGAGCAGAACCCGGCAGAUGGGAAACGCAUCAUAUUCUGAUUCCUACCUGGAAGGAAUUUUGUUGAAAGGGGUUUUCACCUGUGAGCCUUGGUCUGUCUCGGUAGGGUGGUCAACUUCAGUGGACUGUGGUUGGUUUCAGAGCGCCUGGCUGAGGAGUUCCACUGAGGGGAGCACUGGAGCAGCCCUUUGGCAGAGGCUGAGGAGGGAGAUGGACCAGCCCACGCCUGGCACCUGGCUCCAUGGCAUAAGGAAAGGGAGAUGCUGGCCUCUGUGCUCCUGCUGUCUUUUCCUGUUUCUGUUUGCGUUUGACUUAGUAGCAACCGACAGAGUGGCAAGGGAUUUGGUCUUCAGCAGUAGACAUCCUUCCACCCCUGCCCUCAGCCAAGUCUCUUGCUGCCAUGCCAAUGCUAUGUCCACCCUUGCCCCUCGGCCCAAGAGUGUCCAGCGGUGGCCCACCUCUUCCUCCCACUACAGCCUCAACAGUAUGUACCAUCUCCCACUGUAAAUAGUCCCAGUUAGAACGGAAUGCCGUUGUUUUAUAACUUUGAACAAAUGUAUUUACUGCCCUUCUCAUUUCUCCUGGCCAACCUUUAGCCUCACUGACAAAUUAUGACCACAUGUCUACCACACACAGGGACUGGGCACGGCCUGGUGGCUGCCGCAAACAAAAACAUGGCCAGCAGGUAUCCAGUGUCCAGGCAGGAAGAACACAACUUGCAUCCCUGACUGCGGGGAGCUUAGAUGUCAGACCCCGGGCAAGGUGCUUUUACAUAUACCCAUACCAGAUCUUACUAACUCCAUAGGAGAAAUCCGUGUAAUGGGAUUCAGGAAAAUGAAGUAACUUGCACAACAGGGCUCACAGCUUAGAAAGGAGAGAGCUUGGAGUUUUAACCAGAUCUGACCCUCAAGCCCAAGCUAUUUCCAGUUUAUUCCAGGGUGCCUGAACUUGGCUGUUAUGUAUACUGAGUCCUGUGCAGGGCCUCUGACAGCAGGAAGGGGCCCCAAGUCUAAAAUACUUGAAGGGAUUGGGUUACUAGGGCCAUUAUGUUAAGCAAGAGAGCUCGGGGGAAUGCAUUUUAGCUUCAUAUUCCUAUUUAAAAUGUGCUGUGUGGGUGGGUAAAUUGCUUCCAUAAGCUUCACAGUGGCAUUUAAGGCUCCUGGGUUAAGUUAGGAAUGGGGGUGUUCCUGAUGUGGGGGCUUUAGGCUUCCAUGAAGUGGGUCUGGGCCCCCUGCCUUACCUCACAGCCCCCAUCUACCCUGGAAGAGGGAGUUGAAAAUGCUGGGAUAGCAGCAGGAUCAGUUCUCAGCUUGAGCCAAAGCACCCGGCCCUGGGCAGCUGAGCAUCAGCACAGAACCCUCUGAGUCCUUUGGGCUCUCUGCUGAGGAAGACUGCUUCACUCUUCCCGCCCACCAACUCGCUGGCCCAACCAGCAGCUGCUGCUUAAGAAAACACCCACAGACUCACCACAUUUUAGUCUUAGCAUUUACUUUCCCCACCCCACAUUCUUGGAACAGCCUUUAGUUCUACAGGAAAUGGCACUGAUGGACAGAAGACUAGCAUUACCUUCAUGAAAGGGCUGUUAGAGCUGCCUGGGAAGAAGGCGUGCCUUGGGGAACUGGGAAGAUGCCGUCAGUGUGGGUGGGCAGGAGGACAGCCAGUCGUCCUGCUGCCAGCCCAAUAGCUUCCAGCGGCAGGUGCCCAGGUGCUACCGGAGCCCCUCAUAGGGGUAGGGGCAGGGACUGCACCUCCUCCAGGCACUCAUCGUAAGCCUCCUGGUACUCCUCAUGGGGCUUGACCAUUAUCACACAGGUGGGGCGCUUGGAGCCUGCGGCUGCACCCAGGUCCUACAGAGGGGAAAGAAGUGCUGUUUGGAAAAAAGCUGUACAACCUGUAUGCCAGGAAGUCACCAACUGAUGACCCACCAGCCUAAUCUGGCCCACAACCAUGUUCUGUUCGGUCCAUGUUCUAUUUAAAAGCAUCUUGAAUUGGUUGCCAUCAUUUAAACUCAAUCAGACUUUGAAGGCAUGGUCCAGCCACACAGGGCCUACAUUCCCACAUGGCAACUAUGAAAGGGCUCCAGCCCAGCAGGGGCUGUCCCGGUCCCUGCCACCCCCACUUCCUGUGCCUCAGAUCUGGCCCCUGUUACGUAAGAUAAGGACAGCUACAGGUCCCUCUGAGCCUAAACCCACCUAACCGGACUAACAUGGGUGAAGCAUCUUAGCUUACAAAGCUCUUUCACAUACAUCUAUCUCUUUAUUCUCAUAGUCCACAGAUAACUGACUAUUUGGUUCUUACCAUCAGGCCAAACGGUAAGUUCCUUCAGAACAGGGCCUCCUGCUUUAUCCCAAGAAGUGAUACUGUAGGUACCCAAGAUCCACCCCCAGCCUCUAUUUUUUUUUUUUGAGACAGGGCCUCACUCUGUCAUGCAGUCUGGAGUGUGGUGGUGUAUGAUCAUGGCUCACUGCAGCCUUGAACUCCUGGGUUCAAGUGAUCUCCUGCUUUAGCCUCCCAAGUGGCUGGGACUACAGGCAUGUGCCACCACACCCAGCUAAUUAAAAAAAUUUUUUUUGUAGA